CUGCCCGGAGCCCAGCCUCGCUGCCCGGCUGCUCUCUAGGCCCGUUUGGGACUCGAACUGGACAGUGAUGAGGCGCAGAGCGGGGGACCCGGGGCUGCGCCUAGGGACUUCGCGGGGUGCGGAUGCCUCUCUGCACAGGCUGUGGUGCUGCAGCCGGCCCAGCUUCCCCGGUGGGCUGCUGGCUUCCGAACGCGCCGAGGGAUGCGGGGUGCCCGAAGUGGGGAUGUGGUCUCGGGGUGCCAAGGGAGCGGGAGCACCGAGCGCGGGUGGGGGCGGGCGCUCGAAGGGUGGGGCGCGAGGCCGGACCCCGCGGGCACGAUCCCGCACCCAGGGCGCGCAGAGGCUGGGCCCCCUUAGCGCUUCCGAUUGAGGCUCCUCAAGAGAGGCUGAAAUGGGGUGAGAGACCGGGGACGGCCAUUUCGGGGCUAAACGCUGCCAAGGCCAUGACGAUGUUUUAGGAGCUGAACUCUGCUUUCCAAUUAAGCCAUUUUCUUUCUGAGGAAAAGUUGAUUCGGGCUCAUUAACAAGGAUGACUGAGGGCCAUUAUUGGGGCUUAGAGAGAUUCUCCUUUGCCUUGUCUGGCUUCUUUGUUUGCAUGUGCGUGCGUGUGCGGCUGUGUGUGUGUGUGUGAGAGAGAGAGAGAGAGAGAGAGAGAGAGAGAGAGAGAAGAGAGGGGAGAGAGGCAGUGUUGGGGGUGGGAGGAGGUAAAACAGGCUUGGGAUCCUGCAGGCCUGGGUUCCGAUUUGGUUUCCACAGCCUGCUAGUUUAACCUUUCUAAGCUUCAUUGCUCCCAUUUGAUGGCUCAGAUUCUUCCUCUGUAAAAUGCGGACAUUCAUGCCAAUUGGACUGGAGGAGAAGCCACCAAGCACAGUCCCUGACCCAGAGCGAAGCAUGUAUGUGUUGAGUCCUCCUAAUUCGGUGUGAAUUUUUCGGUUCUGUUUUUCUCCUAUGCUGUCUGCACCAGCUCAGCUCAGCUCCGCUCCCCAGCCUUCUCCGCGGCAGCCUCUUCAGCCUGCUGGCCGCAAGUGCGCCCUCUAAAGGCCCCAAAUGCCCUGUACACACCAGGUGAAGAGCGCGGAAGCGCCUGCAGAGCAGAAUUAAAGAAAAAUCUUGGAAAAUGUAUACCAGUCAUGAAGAUAUUGGGUAUGAUUUUGAAGAUGGCCCCAAAGACAAAAAGACACUGAAGCCCCACCCAAACAUUGAUGGCGGAUGGGCUUGGAUGAUGGUGCUCUCCUCUUUCUUUGUGCACAUCCUCAUCAUGGGCUCCCAGAUGGCCCUGGGUGUCCUCAACGUGGAAUGGCUGGAAGAAUUCCACCAGAGCCGCGGCCUGACCGCCUGGGUCAGCUCCCUCAGCAUGGGCAUCACCUUGAUAGUGGGCCUGGGCAGCGGGAUGGCCUACCUGCCAGCGGUGGUCAUGGUGGGCAGGUAUUUCCAGAAGAGACGCGCCCUCGCCCAGGGCCUCAGCACCACGGGGACCGGAUUCGGUACGUUCCUAAUGACUGUGCUGCUGAAGUACCUGUGCGCAGAGUACGGCUGGAGGAAUGCCAUGUUGAUCCAAGGUGCCGUUUCCCUAAACCUGUGUGUUUGUGGGGCGCUCAUGAGGCCCCUCUCUCCUGGUAAAAACCCAAACGACCCAGGAGAGAAAGAUGUGCGUGGCCUGCCAGCGCACUCCACAGAAUCUGUGAAGUCAACUGGACAGCAGGGAAGAACAGAAGAGAAGGAUGGUGGGCUCGGGAACGAGGAGACCCUCUGCGACCUGCAAGCCCAGGAGUGCCCCGAUCAGGCCGGGCACAGGAAGAACAUGUGUGCCCUCCGGAUUCUGAAGACUGUCAGCUGGCUCACCAUGAGAGUCAGGAAGGGCUUCGAGGACUGGUAUUCGGGCUACUUUGGGACAGCCUCUCUAUUUACAAAUCGAAUGUUUGUAGCCUUUAUUUUCUGGGCUUUGUUUGCAUACAGCAGCUUUGUCAUCCCCUUCAUUCACCUCCCAGAAAUCGUCAAUUUGUAUAACUUAUCGGAGCAAAACGACGUUUUCCCUCUGACGUCAAUUAUAGCAAUAGUUCACAUCUUUGGAAAAGUGAUCCUGGGCGUCAUAGCCGACUUGCCUUGCAUUAGUGUUUGGAAUGUCUUCCUGUUGGCCAACUUCACCCUUGUCCUCAGUAUUUUUAUUCUGCCGUUGAUGCACACGUACGCUGGCCUGGCGGUCAUCUGUGCGCUGAUAGGGUUUUCCAGUGGUUAUUUCUCCCUAAUGCCCGUAGUGACUGAAGACUUGGUUGGCAUUGAACACCUGGCCAAUGCCUACGGCAUCAUCAUCUGUGCUAAUGGCAUCUCUGCAUUGCUGGGACCACCUUUUGCAGGGUGGAUCUAUGACAUCACGCAAAAAUAUGAUUUUUCCUUCUACAUAUGUGGUUUGCUUUACAUGAUAGGAAUACUCUUUUUACUUAUUCAGCCGUGCAUUCGAAUUAUAGAACAAUCCAGAAGAAAAUACAUGGAUGGUGCACAUGUUUAGUAUCAUGUAAUGUUCCGUGUAGGUUUCAUUGUAAUACUCAUGCCUACCUCGCAUGGUUGCUGUGAGGCACCUAUGACAGGACGUGGGAAAGCAUUUUGUACGGUAACUGGCACUGUCAUUUGUAAAUGCCAUUGUCACAGCCUCAUUUGUAAGCAGCACUGCCUCUCUGUUUGGGGAGAUGUAAUGCUGGAAGAUCUUAAGGACUACAUACAUUCUAGAGAUGACAGUGUUGUUCAAAGACAGCCUAGUAAGUAAUUGGUAGAAAUGCCCUUAUAAAAACCAUUCUCUUGUCAUCUACUGGGACUAGGGUUUUAAAUACAGCUUUUAAAAACAAAAACAGGGAAUAAAAGCUUUUCAACUCAACCACUUCUUUGUAAGACAAAACUGAAGUAUCUGUGUGCUUCCAGAAAGCUUACAGAUAAAUGGGUUUCAAGCACAAGAAUAUGACUAGAUUUCAGAAAUUAAUUAUUACAGGGAGCUAUUGAUCUACUAGCAUCAAACAAAGGCAAGCUCUAAUUCCACAGGUAAUACAAUUUAGUGCAAUUAAAGAAACACGGCUUGUAUUUUUAUGAGGGAAUUCUGCAGCUAGGGAUUGUGACUCCUAAAUCCUCCUCUAAAAGAAGGCACUUGCCAUUAAUCCUAAUUCAGUGCUAUCCAGUUAUAAAUGGAAUCUUGAGACAAAACCUUAACAAAGAAAUAACAGUAAUGAUUUCCUUAGCAGAAGCCGUAUUUGUACGCACAACAUUAAAUCAAGGGCUACAAUUCAAGCACUUUUAUUCGUAUCAUUGGCCUCUUAGAUGAUAUAAGCAUGAGGUGGGGCCUGUAAUAUUUUUUUCUGAGUUUCUUCUGCCCAAAAAUAUAAUAUAGAACUAAUUGCUAACUGACAAAUAAAGUUAAUAGUUAAAUCAUCUCCAAGGAAUGUUGCUAAUCCAAAGUAUAACACUAUCAAUUUGUGAGGAUAAUAAAUGGAAUGCCAUUAGUGUAGAUGUCUGUGCCACAUCUGACACUGGAGUAGUGAUAACAAAUAGCCCAUCUCUAGACUCUCGUGUUGUUAUAUAGACCAUUCAUUUGCCUGAGCGUGGCACAGUUUUAAAAAUAGUUCUCUUGAUUGAUUUCAUACAGAAGAUGACUGUGAUCCAUGACAUCUAAUAAUGCCCUUUCUUUAUCUGAGAUGUCUAUUUUUCUAAGCCAAACGUUUUUCAGACUGCAGAAUGUUCUUCCCAGAUCAUUUGAAAUUUCUGGCUGCCUUACUUGUUUACAGAUAGUUUAAGACUAUUUAAAUUUCUACUCACAAUUUGAUCAUCACACACACACAAAUCCUUGAAUAUCAUUGCCAGUGUCUUAGGUCAAAUUUACCUAAAGUGAAUACAGCCCAUUCUCAAUUAUCCUUCACAAUUAGACGCAGGAAUGCUACUAGGAAUUGGAAUCAAACAAUGCCACCCCAAGCGUAAUUUUAGCCAGCAGUUUCAGUUAUACUCAACCAUGCCCUUCUGAGCUGUUAACAAGUGAUUCAAUGGACAAGUUCUCUUUUUGUUCCAUCUCCAUUAUUUCCUGCUCUAAUGUAUAGUGGGAGUGGUUGUGUAAUGAAAGGACCACCAAAAUAAUAAAAGGCAGCUAAUGGAAAGGAGAGACAAAAGCAUGGUUAAUAUAUAUACUUAAUAUUACCUCCAAUGACUCGGGAAUUGCCUGUAAAUUAUUAUAGACAAUAGAUUGCAUGUCAUACUCCAUUUGGUUCAACACAACAACCUAUGUGUUAUCAUUACAGCUUUGGCUGCUGUUAAAGAAUCCAGCUCUCUAUUUUGAUAAAGAUAAUCUUAAAGCUGAGGCAAUGCUCCCUCCUCUAUCUCUCUCUGUGUAAUUUACCAUAGAAUUAGGAUGAUUAGAUUGAAACACAUGUUGUAUGUUUUAAAAACUACAUUGCUUCAUUACUUUCAUUUUCCGACAACAUCAAACUAACAAGAGGCAGUGUUAAAUAUUUUAAAUGGUGCUAUAGCCAAUGUAUUUGAAUGCUUGCACUGCUGGUUGUGUAUCAUCAAUAUGAACUUUUUAUCCAAUGACUCAACUCUAAUUACAUCUAAGUUAGACUUGCUCACGUUCAGUUUGUACAGUUGUGUGUUGACUUACUAUGUUUUGAAAGUGGUGACUUCUACCGAAUGAGUGGAAGUUCCCAUUGUCAAAAAAAAUAAAGACCUGCUUGCAGUAUUCAUGUUGACAACAGAGUAAAAGAGAAUACUGUAAAGAAUUACUGCAAAUAUUUCCUGUUUAUGUUAUUUGCCGUUGUUUGAAGAUAUUAUAAAGGGUUAAUUGUAUAUUUAUAUCAUGUGCUUUAUCGUUUUCCCCUCAUGUAUCCAAGUAAUUUUUAUUUACAUACAACUAAAUAAAUGUUGUCCUCUUUGAA